GUUGUCCGCGGUGCUCAGCGCCCGCCCGGGCGCGCCAUGGGGAACCGCAGCACCGCGGACGCGGACGGGCUGCUGGCUGGGCGCGGGCCGGCCGCGGGGGCAUCUGCGGGGGCAUCUGCGGGGCUGGCUGGGCAGGGCGCGGCGGCGCUGGUGGGGGGCGUGCUGCUCAUCGGCGCGGUGCUCGCGGGGAACUCGCUCGUGUGCGUGAGCGUGGCCACCGAGCGCGCCCUGCAGACGCCCACCAACUCCUUCAUCGUGAGCCUGGCGGCCGCCGACCUCCUCCUCGCUCUCCUGGUGCUGCCGCUCUUCGUCUACUCCGAGGUCCAGGGUGGCGCGUGGCUGCUGAGCCCCCGCCUGUGCGACGCCCUCAUGGCCAUGGACGUCAUGCUGUGCACCGCCUCCAUCUUCAACCUGUGCGCCAUCAGCGUGGACAGGUUCGUGGCCGUGGCCGUGCCGCUGCGCUACAACCGGCAGGGUGGGAGCCGCCGGCAGCUGCUGCUCAUCGGCGCCACGUGGCUGCUGUCCGCGGCGGUGGCGGCGCCCGUACUGUGCGGCCUCAACGACGUGCGCGGCCGCGACCCCGCCGUGUGCCGCCUGGAGGACCGCGACUACGUGGUCUACUCGUCCGUGUGCUCCUUCUUCCUACCCUGCCCGCUCAUGCUGCUGCUCUACUGGGCCACGUUCCGCGGCCUGCAGCGCUGGGAGGUGGCACGUCGCGCCAAGCUGCACGGCCGCGCGCCCCGCCGACCCAGCGGCCCUGGCCCGCCUUCCCCCACGCCACCCGCGCCCCGCCUCCCCCAGGACCCCUGCGGCCCCGACUGUGCGCCCCCCGCGCCCGGCCUUCCCCGGGGUCCCUGCGGCCCCGACUGUGCGCCCGCCGCGCCCAGCCUCCCCCAGGACCCCUGCGGCCCCGACUGUGCGCCCCCCGCGCCCGGCCUCCCCCCGGACCCCUGCGGCUCCAACUGUGCUCCCCCCGACGCCGUCAGAGCCGCCGCGCUCCCACCCCAGACUCCACCGCAGACCCGCAGGAGGCGGCGUGCCAAGAUCACCGGCCGGGAGCGCAAGGCCAUGAGGGUCCUGCCGGUGGUGGUCGGGGCCUUCCUGCUGUGCUGGACGCCCUUCUUCGUGGUGCACAUCACGCAGGCGCUGUGUCCUGCCUGCUCCGUGCCCCCGCGGCUGGUCAGCGCCGUCACCUGGCUGGGCUACGUCAACAGCGCCCUCAACCCCGUCAUCUACACUGUCUUCAACGCCGAGUUCCGCAACGUCUUCCGCAAGGCCCUGCGUGCCUGCUGCUGAGCCGGGCACCCCCGGACGCCCCCCGGCCUGAUGGCCAGGCCUCAGGGACCAAGGAGAUGGGGAGGGCGCUUUUGUACGUUAAUUAAACAAAUUCCUUCCCAAA